ACCGUGUGCUGGGACACCCCACAGUCAGCCGCAUGGCUCCCCUGUGCCCCAGCCCCUGGCUCCCUCUGUUGAUCCCGGCCCCUGCUCCAGGCCUCACUGUGCAACUGCUGCUGUCACUGCUGCUUCUGGUGCCUGUCCAUCCCCAGAGGUUGCCCCGGAUGCAGGAGGAUUCCCCCUUGGGAGGAGGCUCUUCUGGGGAAGAUGACCCACUGGGCGAGGAGGAUCUGCCCAGUGAAGAGGAUUCACCCAGAGAGGAGGAUCCACCCGGAGAGGAGGAUCUACCUGGAGAGGAGGAUCUACCUGGAGAGGAGGAUCUACCUGAAGUUAAGCCUAAAUCAGAAGAAGAGGGCUCCCUGAAGUUAGAGGAUCUACCUACUGUUGAGGCUCCUGGAGAUCCUCAAGAACCCCAGAAUAAUGCCCACAGGGACAAAGAAGGGGAUGACCAGAGUCAUUGGCGCUAUGGAGGCGACCCGCCCUGGCCCCGGGUGUCCCCAGCCUGCGCGGGCCGCUUCCAGUCCCCGGUGGAUAUCCGCCCCCAGCUCGCCGCCUUCUGCCCGGCCCUGCGCCCCCUGGAACUCCUGGGCUUCCAGCUCCCGCCGCUCCCAGAACUGCGCCUGCGCAACAAUGGCCACAGUGUGCAACUGACCCUGCCUCCUGGGCUAGAGAUGGCUCUGGGUCCCGGGCGGGAGUACCGGGCUCUGCAGCUGCAUCUGCACUGGGGGGCUGCAGGUCGUCCGGGCUCGGAGCACACUGUGGAAGGCCACCGUUUCCCUGCCGAGAUCCACGUGGUUCACCUCAGCACCGCCUUUGCCAGAGUUGACGAGGCCUUGGGGCGCCCGGGAGGCCUGGCCGUGUUGGCCGCCUUUCUGGAGGAGGGCCCGGAAGAAAACAGUGCCUAUGAGCAGUUGCUGUCUCGCUUGGAAGAAAUCGCUGAGGAAGGCUCAGAGACUCAGGUCCCAGGACUGGACAUAUCUGCACUCCUGCCCUCUGACUUCAGCCGCUACUUCCAAUAUGAGGGGUCUCUGACUACACCGCCCUGUGCCCAGGGUGUCAUCUGGACUGUGUUUAACCAGACAGUGAUGCUGAGUGCUAAGCAGCUCCACACCCUCUCUGACACCCUGUGGGGACCUGGUGACUCUCGGCUACAGCUGAACUUCCGAGCGACGCAGCCUUUGAAUGGGCGAGUGAUUGAGGCCUCCUUCCCUGCUGGAGUGGACAGCAGUCCUCGGGCUGCUGAGCCAGUCCAGCUGAAUUCCUGCCUGGCUGCUGGUGACAUCCUAGCCCUGGUUUUUGGCCUCCUUUUUGCUGUCACCAGCGUCGCGUUCCUUGUGCAGAUGAGAAGGCAGCACAGAAGGGGAACCAAAGGGGGUGUGAGCUACCGCCCAGCAGAGGUAGCCGAGACUGGAGCCUAGAGGCUGGAUCUUGGAGAAUGUGAGAAGCCAGCCAGAGGCAUCUGAGGGGGAGCCGGUAACUGUCCUGUCCUGCUCAUUAUGCCACUUCCUUUUAACUGCCAAGAAAUUUUUUAAAAUAAAUAUUUAUAAUAAAA